AGUCGGCGCCAAAAUCAAACGCGUCCUGGCCUGUCCCGCCCCUCUCCCCAAGCGCGGGCCCGGCCAGCGGAAGCCCCUGCGCCCGCGCCAUGUCAAAGAAAAAAGGACUGAGUGCAGAAGAAAAGAGAACUCGCAUGAUGGAAAUAUUUUCUGAAACAAAAGAUGUAUUUCAAUUAAAAGACUUGGAGAAGAUUGCUCCCAAAGAGAAAGGCAUUACUGCUAUGUCAGUAAAAGAAGUCCUUCAAAGCUUAGUUGAUGAUGGUAUGGUUGACUGUGAGAGGAUCGGAACUUCUAAUUAUUAUUGGGCUUUUCCAAGUAAAGCUCUUCAUGCAAGGAAACAUAAGUUGGAGGUUCUGGAAUCUCAGAUGAAGAAACUGAGACACAGAGAGAUUAAGAGCUUGUCCAAGGUCUCACAGAAACAACGUGCAUAUUCAUCACUCAGCAAAUUUUUAAAAUCUUAGUUAUGAAUUUAGAAACUUUAUACAAGGUAAUUUACUUAUGGGCCUUACUGAACUUCCCUGUCUUCAUGUUUUUUUGUUCUUGCUUUUAUCCUUUUUGAGAAUUCCCUUUUCUCUCCUCUCUAUUUAGCCAAAUUCUAAACAUCUCUCCUCUCAGAAACCUCCUCAAGCUCUCAUUGCUUAAAAUAUUCUUACCCUUCUCUAACCUCCUGUAAUAUUUUUUAUCACAAGUAAAAUAUAUUGCUUUGGCAUGUACUGCUGGUUGCCUAGCUAGUCAACAUUGUCCUCCUCUUCUUCACUAACAAAACACUUUGUUAAAGGAUAGUGUGUCUUACUAAAAAAUACUCAUCUUUCCAGACUCCCUGGCAACUAAUGGUGGCAAUGGGAAGCAGGUCUGAUAAAUGAGAUGUAAGUAGAAGACUAGCUUUGACUUUCCUGGGAAAGUUUUCACUUUCCUGAAAAAGGCAAAGCUUCUUUCUCCUCUUUUCUGUGAUAUGCAUUACUGAGAUAAAAAGCAUAAGGAUGAAAGUUCUGUUCAUUCAUGUCCAUAUCACAUUCUCAAAGAAUGACAGAGCCUGGAAAAAAGAUCUUGGGUCUCUGGUGGCAUCAUGAGAUACUGUACUAGCCUUAUUUAAUCCAGUUUUAGUUAAAUAUUGUUAUUUGUGGCCGAAUGUGUAUUCUAAAUGAAUACUACUGUUUUGUAGCCUUUAAAAAAAAAGUGUGAUUUAGAUUUUGUAUUAGUUAUCCAUUGCUAUGUAACAAAAAUAUGUACUCCAAAACAGGGUGACUUUAAGAAAUACCAAAACAGGGUGACUUUAAGAAAUAGACAUUACUAUCUCACAGUUCUUGUGACUCGUGAAUCCCAGCAUGGCUUAGUUGGGUACAUCUGGCUCAAGGCCUUAUGUGAGGUAUAGUCAAACUGUUGGCCAGGGCCAUAUUCUCAUCUGAAGGUUUAUCUGGGAGAGGAUCUGCUUCCAAAUCCAAUCAUGUGGUUAUUGGAUUUAGUUCCUUGCAGGGUCUUGGGCUGCAGAUCUCAGUUCUAUGAUGGCUUUUGGCCCAAGGCCUCCCUCAGCUCCUUACCACAUGGUUUUCUCCGUAGUACAGCUCACAGUAUGGCAGCUGGCUUCUCUCAAAGCAAGCUCAUGUGUGAGAGUCCAAGACAGAAGCAGUAGUUUUUUUGUAUCUUAAUCUAGGAAACAACAUCCCAUCACCUCAGCCACAUUUUAUUCCCUAGAAACAAGUCAUUAAAUUUAGUUUACACUCAAGAGAGGAGAUUACACAUGAGCAUAAAUACAGGCAUACCUCAGAUAUUGCAGGUUCAGUUCCAUACCACCACAAUAAAGGGAAUAAUGCAAUAAAGUGAGGACAGAAACUUUUUGGUUUCUCAGUGCACCUAAAAGUUAUAUUUAUACUAUACUGUAAUCUAUUAAAUAUGUGAUAACAUGUUUUUAAAAACUAAUGUACAUUAAUUUAAAAAUACUUUAUUGCUAAAAAAUGCUGAUGAGCAUCUGAGCCUUCUGUGAGUUGUAAUCUUUUUGCAGGUGGAGGGUAUUGCCUUGAUCUUGAUGGCUGCUGACUGAUCAGGGUGAUGGUUGCUGAAGGGUAGAUGGCUAUAGUCGUUUUUUAAAAAUAAGACAACCGUGAAGUUUGCUCCAUUGAUUGAUUUCACAAAAGAUUUCUCUGUAGCAUGUGAUGCUGUUUGAUAGCAUUUUACCCACAACAGAACUUUGAAAAUUAGA